GCGAGUCCAGAGGCAGGCGAGCAGCUCGGUCGCCCCCACCGGCCCCAUGGCAGCCCCCGGCGCCCCAGCUGAGUACGGCUACAUCCGGACCGUCCUGGGCCAGCAGAUCCUGGGACAACUGGACAGCUCCAGCCUGGCGCUGCCCUCCGAGGCCAAGCUGAAGCUGGCGGGGAGCAGCGGCCGCGGCGGCCAGACAGUCAAGAGCCUGCGGAUCCAGGAGCAGGUGCAGCAGACCCUCGCCCGGAAGGGCCGCAGCUCCGUGGGCAACGGUCCAGUGCUAAACUGAAACCAAAUCAGCUUCCCCUGCGUAGGAGACACAGGAGGCAUAUUAGAUAUUCUUUCUUAUCCUCUGAGAAUGGCCAGCUAGGAAGAGAGCAAGCAGAUACAACUCUUCCAUAAAUGGAGGGAAUGGAGCCAUGAACAGAAGAAAAGGGAAUGUUGCUGAGCAUCUACUAUGUGCCUAUUCCAGAAUCUUCAUUAUAUUCUUGAAACAAUUGCUGAGAUAGAUAUGAGAAUCCAUCUCACAUAUGAAGUAUGUGUCUGUCAGCAAUGGUUGGAAAUUUAAUCCCAACUCCACACAUAAUCUGUUCUUUCUACAAAGUAAUGCAUCACCUGUGUGAUGAAUUCAGCAAGCAUCAAAUGAGUAUGUUCUUCAUGCCGGGCGCUGUGCAGGUGCUGAAUUAAACACAAAGACUCUGCUUGCUUUAAAGCAAAAAGUUUGAAGAAGGAAGCCAACCGCUAGAAAAAUACAUUACCAAAUAAAAAGUAGAAAUCUUCACCGAACCAGCAGUGUUCCUGAGUAUGUCUACAACCUACACUUGGUUGAAAAUGAUUUUGUUGGAGGCCGUUCCCCUGUUCCUAAAACCUAUGACAUGCUAAAGGCUGGCACAACUGCCACUUAUGAAGGUCGCUGGGGAAGAGGAACAGCACAGUACAGCUCCCAGAAGUCCGUGGAAGAAAGGUCCUUGAGGCAUCCUCUGAGGAGACUGGAGAUUUCUCCUGACAGCAGCCCGGAGAGGGCUCACUACACGCACAGCGAUUACCAGUACAGCCAGAGAAGCCAGGCUGGGCACACCCUGCACCACCAAGAAAGCAGGCGGGCCGCCCUCCUAGUGCCACCGAGAUAUGCUCGUUCCGAGAUCGUGGGGGUCAGCCGUGCUGGCACCACAAGCAGGCAGCGCCACUUUGACACAUACCACAGACAGUACCAGCAUGGCUCUGUUAGCGACACCGUUUUUGACAGCAUCCCUGCCAACCCGGCCCUGCUCACGUACCCCAGGCCAGGGACCAGCCGCAGCAUGGGCAACCUCUUGGAGAAGGAGAACUACCUGACGGCAGGGCUCACUGUCGGGCAGGUCAGGCCGCUGGUGCCCCUGCAGCCCGUCACUCAGAACAGGGCUUCCAGGUCCUCCUGGCAUCAGAGCUCCUUCCACAGCACCCGCACGCUGAGGGAAGCUGGGCCCAGUGUCGCCGUGGAUUCCAGCGGGAGGAGAGCGCACUUGACUGUCGGCCAGGCGGCCGCAGGGGGAAGUGGGAAUCUGCUCACUGAGAGAAGCACUUUCACUGACUCCCAGCUGGGGAAUGCAGACAUGGAGAUGACUCUGGAGCGAGCAGUGAGUAUGCUCGAGGCAGACCACAUGCUGCCAUCCAGGAUUUCUGCUGCAGCUACUUUCAUACAGCACGAGUGCUUCCAGAAAUCUGAAGCUCGGAAGAGGGUUAACCAGCUUCGUGGCAUCCUCAAGCUUCUGCAGCUCCUAAAAGUUCAGAAUGAAGACGUUCAGCGAGCUGUGUGUGGGGCCUUGAGAAACUUAGUAUUUGAAGACAAUGACAACAAAUUGGAGGUGGCUGAACUAAAUGGGGUACCUCGGCUGCUCCAGGUGCUGAAGCAAACCAGAGACUUGGAGACUAAAAAACAAAUAACAGGUUUGCUGUGGAAUUUGUCAUCUAAUGACAAACUCAAGAAUCUCAUGAUAACAGAAGCAUUGCUUACGCUGACGGAGAAUAUCAUCAUCCCCUUUUCUGGGUGGCCUGAAGGAGACUACCCAAAAGCAAAUGGUUUGCUCGAUUUUGACAUAUUCUACAACGUCACUGGAUGCCUAAGAAACAUGAGUUCUGCUGGCGCUGAUGGGAGAAAAGCGAUGAGAAGAUGUGACGGACUCAUUGACUCACUGGUCCAUUAUGUCAGAGGAACCAUUGCAGAUUACCAGCCAGAUGACAAGGCCACGGAGAAUUGUGUGUGCAUUCUUCAUAACCUCUCCUACCAGCUGGAGGCAGAGCUCCCAGAGAAAUAUUCCCAGAAUAUCUAUAUUCAAAACCGGAAUAUCCAGACUGACAACAACAAAAGUAUUGGAUGUUUUGGCAGUCGAAGCAGGAAAGUAAAAGAGCAAUACCAGGACGUGCCGAUGCCGGAGGAAAAGAGCAACCCCAAGGGCGUGGAGUGGCUGUGGCAUUCCAUUGUUAUAAGGAUGUAUCUGUCCUUGAUCGCCAAAAGUGUCCGCAACUACACACAAGAAGCAUCCUUAGGAGCUCUGCAGAACCUCACGGCCGGAAGUGGACCAAUGCCGACAUCAGUGGCUCAGACAGUUGUCCAGAAGGAAAGUGGCCUGCAGCACACCCGAAAGAUGCUGCAUGUUGGUGACCCAAGUGUGAAAAAGACAGCCAUCUCGCUGCUGAGGAAUCUGUCCCGGAAUCUUUCUCUGCAGAAUGAAAUUGCCAAAGAAACUCUCCCUGAUUUGGUUUCCAUCAUUCCUGACACAGUCCCGAGUACUGACCUUCUCAUUGAAACUACAGCCUCUGCCUGUUACACAUUGAACAACAUAAUCCAAAACAGUUACCAGAAUGCACGCGACCUUCUAAACACCGGGGGCAUCCAGAAAAUUAUGGCCAUUAGUGCAGGCGAUGCCUAUGCCUCCAACAAAGCAAGUAAAGCUGCUUCCGUCCUUCUGUAUUCUCUGUGGGCACACACGGAACUGCAUCAUGCCUACAAGAAGGCUCAGUUUAAGAAGACAGAUUUUGUCAACAGCCGGACUGCCAAAGCCUACCACUCCCUUAAAGACUGAGGAAAAUGACAAAGUAUUCUCGGCUGCAAAAAUCCCCAAAGGAAAACACCUAUUUUUCUACUACCCAGCCCAAGAAACCUCAAAAGCAUGCCUUGUUUCUAUCCUUCUCUAUUUCCGUGGUCCCCUGAAUCCAGAAAACAAAUAGAACAUAAUUUUAUGAGUCUUCCAGAAGACCUUUGCAAGUUUGCCACCAGUAGAUACCGGCCACAGGCUCGACAAAUAGUGGUCUUUGUUAUUAGGGCUUAUGGUACAUGGCUUCCUGGAAUCAAAAUGUGAAUUCAUGUGGAAGGGACAUUAAUCCAAUAAAUAAGGAAAGAAGCUGUUGCAUUACUGGGAUUUUAAAAGUUUGAUUUACAUUUAUAUUCCUUUUCUGGUUCCCAUGUUUUGUCACUCAUGUGCACAUUGCUUCGCCAUUGGGCCUCCAGUGUAUUGUUCUGCAGUGUUGAAACAGAAUGGAAAUGACAAGAAAUAUCUGCAGUUAUCCAGGAGAAAGUAUAAUGGCAAAAUUAUUGGUUUCUUUCUUUACUUUGUGCUUGUUUUUAUCCCCUUGGGUUGUUUUUCUCUGAUUUUUAAAUAAACUUAAGAAAUUUAGAUUACAGAGUAUGCAUGACUGUAAGAAAAAGAAAUUGAGAGGAAGUGAUCAUAGCAAAUUAAAGAAGUCUUUUCCUCCCAGAACUUAAAGUAAAAUAAAAAAUAAAUAAAUAAAUAAAAUCUUUUCCACAGAGAAAGGCAACUGUGAUGAUAAAAUUUAACGUUCCCCCAAACACUGAGUCAAUGAGAUUUUUCUCAGGAGAUACUUUACCUAUAACAACGCCGUUAAAUCCAAAUCUCUUCUAAACGAUGGCAUUCUAUGUAAUGCCUUUCCUGGACUUUUUUGGCCACUGCCCUGGACUAGUGAAAGAAUGGACUCUAUCUUUAUCUGCAAGAGGAACUAAGGCCUUCUCUCAGACUGCCUGGCCAGCCUGGGGCACUGAAAAUACGGCUCAUGUUAAUGAGUUACAUUAUCAGCCAGCCCAGCCUUGCCCACCAUUUAAGAAAUAUCACAGAGCCACUAGAUCUCAUAUGAUCUUCUUCAAGCCAUUAUUUUAACUCAAGAAAACUCUAGAGAAGAAAAGUGAAGAAGUCAUGUUGAAGAAGAUGUAAGAAUGUGUCAAGACCAUCCAGAAAUGAUAUGAGAAAUACUGAUAUUUUAAAUGGUUGACAUCAUCCAGCGAAAUGAAUCUACAUUAAAUGUUGUUUUAACUGCGCUAUGAUUAAAACCAUUCAUAUAGAGUUAGUCUUUACAACUACUAUUCUGUUAUUUUUUUUUUUAAUCUGACAACAUUUGUCCUAAGUAAGAUAAGCAAAAAAAUUCUUCAACUCCUUUUGGCAAGAAAACUGUAACAGAAAAUAAAUUUUGAAUGUGUACUUAAGUCUUUAUUAUAUUUGAAGCAAUUUUUUUUCAAUUUUAAAAGCUGAAUGAAGACAACUUAGGUUGCUAACCUAGUUCAAAAUGAAAUUAUUUAGAUACCAAUUUUUAAAAUACUGGAGAGAAUUUAUAUGUCUUUUUCCAGAGUUCUGAUGAUAAGCAUUUGGAGUGCAUUUAUUCCUCCAGAUAAUAAAUGUGUGUUCAGAACUUUUUGUGUUUUUUAAGGCAUUAAUAAAGCCUUCGAUAAUAUUAAAUACAAAA